UACUGGAGAGCAACCCUACAAAUGUAAAGAAUGUGGCAAAGCUUUUAAACAUCCUGCAACCCUUUCUUCACAUAACAAAACUCAUACUGGAGAGAAACCAUACAAGUGUGAUAAAUGUGGCAAAGCCUUUAUUUCAUCCUCAACCCUUAGUAAACAUGAGAAGAUUCAUACUGGAGAGAAACCCUACAAAUGUGAAGAAUAUGGCAAAGCUUUCACCCAUUCCUCACACCUUACUAGGCAUAAGAAAAUUCAUGCUGGAGAGAAACCAUACAAGUGUGAUAAAUGUGGCACAGCCUUUAUUUUAUCCUCAACCCUUAGUGAACAUGAGAAGAUUCAUACUGGAGAGAAACUCUACAAAUGUGAAGAAUGUGGCAAAGCCUUCAACCAUUUUUCACACCUUACUAUACAUAAGACAAUUCAUACUGGAGAGAAAUGCUAUAAAUGGUAUAAAAACCUUUACAUGGUCCUCAAGCCCCCAUAAACAUAGGAGAACUCAUACUGGAGAGAAACCUUACAAAUGUGAAGAAUGUGGCAAAGCCUUUACUGCAUCCUCAACUCUAAGUGAAUAUAAGACAAUUCAUACUGGAGAGAAACCUUGCAAAUGUGAAGAAUGUGGCAAAGCUUUUAACUGGUCCUCAGACUUCAAUAAACAUAAGAGAAUUCAUAGUGGACAGAAACCAAUACUGUAACAAAGCUUUAUUUAUUUAUUUAUCUAUUUAUUUAUUUAUUUAUUUAUUUAUUUUUGAGAUGGAGUUUCACUCUUGUUG